GAGUCCGAGGCGCUGGGCCAGGCCGGAGCCGGACUACGGGAGCCGAGGCGGGCCGCGCGGUGGGCGCGGAGAGGAGCGGAGCGGCGCGGCAGGCCGGGCGGGUGGCGGCAGCAGCGGAGGAGGCCGCAGCUGCGGGUCCGAGGAGCGGAGGCGACGCGGGCGGCGGCGGGGGGCCGGGUGGCCGGGGUCCCGGGCCCCGCGGCGGCGGCAGCGGCGGCGGCGGCGGCAGGAUGAUCAAGCUGUUCUCGCUGAAGCAGCAGAAGAAGGAGGAGGAGUCGGCGGGCGGCACCAAGGGCAGCAGCAAGAAGGCGUCGGCGGCGCAGCUGCGGAUCCAGAAGGACAUAAACGAGCUGAACCUGCCCAAGACGUGUGAUAUCAGCUUCUCAGAUCCAGACGACCUCCUCAACUUCAAGCUGGUCAUCUGUCCUGAUGAGGGCUUCUACAAGAGUGGGAAGUUUGUGUUCAGUUUUAAGGUGGGCCAGGGUUACCCGCAUGAUCCCCCCAAGGUGAAGUGUGAGACAAUGGUCUAUCACCCCAACAUUGACCUCGAGGGCAACGUCUGCCUCAACAUCCUCAGAGAGGACUGGAAGCCAGUCCUUACGAUAAACUCCAUAAUUUAUGGCCUGCAGUAUCUCUUCUUGGAGCCCAACCCCGAGGACCCACUGAACAAGGAGGCCGCAGAGGUCCUGCAGAACAACCGGCGGCUGUUUGAGCAGAACGUGCAGCGCUCCAUGCGGGGUGGCUACAUCGGCUCCACCUACUUUGAGCGCUGCCUGAAAUAGGGUUGGCGCAUACCCACCCCCGCCACGGCCACAAGCCCUGGCAUCCCCUGCAAAUAUUUAUUGGGGGCCAUGGGUAGGGGUUUGGGGGGCGGCCGGUGGGGGAAUCCCCUGCCUUGGCCUUGCCUCCCCUUCCUGCCACGUGCCCCUAGUUAUUUUUUUUUUUUUAACACCAUGUGAUUAAGGUCGGCGCUGCCUCCCCCGACCCACUCAGCGAUGGGAAAUGAAUUGGCUUGUCUAGCCCCCCUGCUGGGUGCUUGUUCAGCCCCCACUCUGGGCUGUGGAGUGGGUGGGCAACGGGCCUGGGUAGCUGGGCCCAGGCAACCCACCCCUCCACCUCUGGAGGUCCCACCAGGCUAUUAAAGGGGAAUGUUACUGCA